AAGCGCCGGUGCGCGCGCUGCCCUGGGUUGCCGGCGAGGAGGCCGCGGGAGCGCCUGGACCCGGCCCGCCCAGCCCGGCCCCCGCCCGGCCCCCGCCUCGGCCCCGGCGGGGGAGGGGUCUCUGAGCGCGGCCCCUCCCCCCUGCGCCCCCGCCUGCGCUGCGGUGCCCCCAUCCCGCGUGUCCCAGUCUGUCUGACCGUCCCUCCGCUCCCAGGCCUCGCCCCACCCGGCCCUGGGGCUGCCCGGUCGCCCCCCUCCCCACCGCAGCCGGUCCCCUCCCUCCCAGUCAGCCUCCGCCGCAGCCCAGGAAGCCAGCCGGGACGCCGCCGCCCCGGACCCCGCGCCCUAACCUCCACCUCGGGGGCCUGCACCCCCAGAUUGAAUCGGGAAUUCCGGAAACCCGAGCCUGGAACCCUGAUCUGGGACCAGCACCCCGAGAUCCGGCCGUGGAACCCCAAGAUCUGGAGCCUGAACCCCAGUAUAUGGGGCUGGAAUCUCAACAUCGGUCACUGGGACCUCAAUAUUUGGAGCCGGAACCCCACAAUUUGGAACACAGACCCCAAUAUUUGGAGCAGAACCCCAAGAUUUGACAUCUAAAACCUCAAGCCUGGAGCUGAACUCUGAAUUCUGGGCCUGGGACCUUGAAAUCUGGGACUGGAUUUCCAGUACUGUACCCUGGAACCCACUCUUGGGGACCUGAACCCUGGGAUUCAGGCCUCAAAUUCCAAGAUCUGGACUGUGGGAUUCCAAGGGGCCUGAACCCGAGUUUGGGCCUGAAGUCCUUGCUGCAGACCUGAGUGCUUAAAUCUGGGGCUUGAGACCUCCCAAUCUUGACUCAGCACCCCAAUAUCUGAAUGCAGAACCCCGGGAUCGGAUCUCAGACUCUAAACCCCACCGUUUGGCUGCUUAGCAUCCCAAGACUGGACCUGGGAGACCCUGACCCUGAACAACCCAAACUGGACCCGUAAAACUGGACCCUAGAGGCCCAAUAUUUAGGGGUCUGGAACCCCGAGUAUUAAGGUCUGGAGACUCCGUUGCCACAGAUUUGAGCCGAGUCAGGACACAGUCCCUCUACAGAAGCCUUGGGGACAGGAAAAGCAUGACCAGAUGCUCCCUCCAGAGCCCUGACCUCUGACUCCCCUGGAGCUAGGACUCUGCUCCCUGGGGCUGCUUCUAGCUCAGGACACCCCUGCCCGCGAUGGCCAUCCUCCCGUUGCUCCUGUGCCUGCUGCCGCUGGCCCCUGCCUCAUCCCCACCCCAGUCAGCCACACCCAGCCCAUGUCCCCGCCGCUGCCGCUGCCAGACACAGUCGCUGCCCCUAAGCGUGCUGUGCCCAGGGGCAGGCCUCCUGUUCGUGCCACCCUCGCUGGACCGCCGGGCAGCCGAGCUGCGGCUGGCAGACAACUUCAUCGCCUCCGUGCGCCGCCGCGACCUGGCCAACAUGACAGGCCUGCUGCAUCUGAGCCUGUCGCGGAACACCAUCCGCCACGUGGCUGCCGGCGCCUUCGCCGACCUGCGGGCCCUGCGUGCCCUGCACCUGGAUGGCAACCGGCUGACCUCACUGGGCGAGGGCCAGCUGCGCGGCCUGGUCAACUUGCGCCACCUCAUCCUCAGCAACAACCAGCUGGCAGCGCUGGCGGCCGGCGCCCUGGAUGAUUGUGCCGAGACACUGGAGGACCUCGACCUCUCCUACAACAACCUCGAGCAGCUGCCCUGGGAGGCCCUGGGCCGCCUGGGCAACGUCAACACGUUGGGCCUCGACCACAACCUGCUGGCUUCUGUGCCCGCCGGCGCUUUUUCCCGCCUGCACAAGCUGGCCCGGCUGGACAUGACCUCCAACCGCCUGACCACAAUCCCACCCGACCCACUCUUCUCCCGCCUGCCCCUGCUCGCCAGGCCCCGGGGCUCGCCCGCCUCUGCCCUGGUGCUGGCCUUUGGCGGGAACCCCCUGCACUGCAACUGCGAGCUGGUGUGGCUGCGUCGCCUGGCGCGGGAGGACGACCUCGAGGCCUGCGCGUCCCCACCUGCUCUGGGCGGCCGCUACUUCUGGGCGGUGGGCGAGGAGGAGUUUGUCUGCGAGCCGCCCGUGGUGACUCACCGCUCACCACCUCUGGCUGUGCCCGCAGGUCGGCCGGCUGCCCUGCGCUGCCGGGCAGUGGGGGACCCAGAGCCCCGUGUGCGUUGGGUGUCACCCCAGGGCCGGCUGCUAGGCAACUCAAGCCGUGCCCGCGCCUUCCCCAAUGGGACGCUGGAGCUGCUGGUCACCGAGCCGGGUGAUGGUGGCAUCUUCACCUGCAUUGCGGCCAAUGCAGCUGGCGAGGCCACAGCUGCUGUGGAGCUGACUGUGGGUCCCCCACCACCUCCUCAGCUAGCCAACAGCACCAGCUGUGACCCCCCGCGGGACGGGGAUCCUGAUGCUCUCACCCCACCCUCCGCUGCCUCUGCUUCUGCCAAGGUGGCCGACACUGGGCCCCCUACCGACCGUGGCGUCCAGGUGACUGAGCACGGGGCCACAGCUGCUCUUGUCCAGUGGCCGGAUCAGCGGCCUAUCCCGGGCAUCCGCAUGUACCAGAUCCAGUACAACAGCUCGGCUGAUGACAUCCUCGUCUACAGGAUGAUCCCGGCGGAGAGCCGCUCGUUCCUGCUGACGGACCUGGCGUCAGGCCGGACCUACGAUCUGUGCGUGCUCGCCGUGUAUGAGGACAGCGCCACGGGGCUCACGGCCACGCGGCCUGUGGGCUGCGCCCGCUUCUCCACCGAACCUGCGCUGCGGCCAUGCGGGGCGCCGCACGCUCCCUUCCUGGGCGGCACGAUGAUCAUCGCGCUGGGCGGCGUCAUCGUAGCCUCGGUACUGGUCUUCAUCUUCGUGCUGCUAAUGCGCUACAAGGUGCACGGCGGCCAGCCCCCCGGCAAGGCCAAGAUUCCCGCGCCUGUUAGCAGCGUUUGCUCCCAGACCAACGGCGCCCUGGGCCCCACGCCCACGCCCGCCCCGCCCGCCCCGGAGCCCGCGGCGCUCAGGGCCCACACCGUGGUCCAGCUGGACUGCGAGCCCUGGGGGCCCGGCCACGAACCUGUGGGACCCUAGCCAGGCGCCCCCCCCUCUAAGGGUCCUCUGGCCCCACGGACAGCAGGACCCGGACACCCUGUGGGACCUGGCCUCAAACUCACCAAAUCGCUCAUGGUUUUUAAAACUCUGAUGGGGAGGGUGUCGGGGACACCGGGGCAAAACAAGAAAGUCCUAUUUUUCCAAGCUUGGGCGAAGACCCUUGCCCUCGUCUCUGUCUAUGGGGGUUGGGGGACGGAGCAGGGGUCUGGAGCUGGGGAAUGCCUCCUUUGGGGAGACACCCCCUCCCCGCCCAGUUCAGUCUGAGGACCCCGGAGGAGGCUGAGGAUGGCGAUCCAUUCAGACAAUAGAUGUUCCCUGCGUGUCGGCUCUGAGCAUGCCCUGGGUUGGGGGAUGCUGUGGUGAUCCAGAUAGCCCUGAGCCCUGCCCGCAGGGGCCUAAAGUCAAAUGGGAGACAGACACAUCCCCAGACAGUGAUAGCACAGAGUGACCAGGGAUGUGGGGAUGAGGGAAGCCUGGGGGAUUGUGACAGUCCAGAAGAGGUACCCUUGCUCAGCCCCAGGUGUGGUCAGGGAGGGCUUCCUGGAGGAGGACACAUGUGAUCUGAGAAUGACAUAUGAAGGAGAUAACUGGGCAAAGAGCAGAAGGAAAGCUCUUUCAGGCAGAGGGCACAGCACAAGCAAGGUGGUGGUGUGCCCUGGGCACUGGGGGUGCUAUGGUAGAGGUGAGGCAGGAGGGUUGAGCAGGGUCUAGGACCUCCAGGCUGAGGAGCUCAGACUCUGGCCUGAUGAUACCAGGGAGCCAUGGAGGGUUGUAUGCAAGGGAGGAAUGGGGUCAGUUUGGGGCUUCAGGAAGAUCCUUCUAGUGCUAUGAGUAGGGUGGACCCAAGGGGAAGACUGAAGCUGGGAGCCCCAGGGGAAGCUGGGGCAGGGACCUGGGUGGGUGAGGACGAAGUUGGACCAGCUGGGCUAGGGAACAAGAAAAGGGAGUGGGUUGACAGAGACACUCGGGAAACUGUGGGAAGCUGAGGCGGUGGGUUAUGGAGCUGCGGGGCCAUGGGGUGGGGCAGGAAGAUGGUGGGGACUGCCCUCAUAUAGGACCAGGGAGGAGGAGCAGGUUUGGGAAAGAUGAUAUGGCCAGUGGGGAACUUGGUAGGUGUAGGGGGCCCUGAGGAUGUCCAGGAUGUGGCAUUCAGGAGGGUGCAGGACCCCUGGUCUGAGGCUGAAGCUGGAAAUAGAAAUGAGGGCUUUGUCAGCAGAGAUGGGAACUGACGCUGCUGGGGUUAAGACGGCUUCUUGUGGGGGAUGAUUCCAAGUCCCCACUAUGGGACAUUUUUUCUUUUUUCUUUUUUUUUUUUACAGAUGGGGUCUCACUAUAUUGCCCAGGCUGAUCCCAAACUGGCCUCAAGUGAUCCUCCCGUCUCAGCCUCCUGAAUUGCUGGGAUUACAGGCAUGAGCCACUGCCCCUGGCUAGGGACUUUCCAUAUUUAAGGGUGACGCAAAGAAAAACCUAACCAAGACUAAACAGGACCAGCAGGCAGAGGGACAGGGGGAAGAAGACCAAGCAAUUCAGACCCAAGAAACUCUUGUGUUCAAUGAUAUAAAUAAAGGCUGCGGUGACCCCCCA